AGUCUCCGCCCGGCGCUCCCGGGAUCAGCUGGCGGGCGGGCGGGAGCCGAGCGCGGCCCCGGCUCUCGCUGCAGCGCCGCCUCUUCUCUGCGUCGCAGGCCGGCCCGGCGGCCGUGACAAUGUCGCGGGGCUGGUAGCAGGGCGCCGGCCGCCGAGCCGUCUCAAGUUUAAACUUACACGAAUCGCUUUCUGGAGGAGGAGGGGACCCGCUGCGCGAUUGACACGCAUAUUCCUAUAGGCAUCCUCCCUCAGCCCCCACCCCCACGGCCGGAUUCGGGUGGCUCCUCUCCGAGGUGAAAUCUGAGAAGAAAUCCUUGGAUCUCUUUUCUUAAAAAAAAAAAAAAAAAAAAAAAAUCUAGAAACCAUCGGUAUUUUGCUUUGCUGCUCCCUAUUCGCAAGAUGAAGAAGUUUUUCGACUCCCGGCGAGAGCAGGGCGGCUCUGGCCUGGGCUCCGGCUCCAGCGGAGGAGGGGGCAGCACCUCGGGCCUGGGCAGUGGCUACAUCGGAAGAGUCUUCGGCAUCGGGCGACAGCAGGUCACAGUGGACGAGGUGUUGGCGGAAGGUGGAUUUGCUAUUGUAUUUCUGGUGAGGACAAGCAAUGGGAUGAAAUGUGCCUUGAAACGCAUGUUUGUCAACAAUGAGCAUGAUCUCCAGGUGUGCAAGAGAGAAAUCCAGAUAAUGAGGGAUCUUUCAGGGCACAAGAAUAUUGUGGGUUACAUUGAUUCUAGUAUCAACAACGUGAGUAGCGGUGAUGUAUGGGAAGUGCUCAUUCUGAUGGACUUUUGUAGAGGUGGCCAGGUGGUAAACCUGAUGAACCAGCGCCUGCAAACAGGCUUUACAGAGAAUGAAGUGCUCCAGAUAUUUUGUGAUACCUGUGAAGCUGUUGCCCGCCUGCAUCAGUGCAAAACUCCUAUUAUCCACCGGGACCUGAAGGUUGAAAACAUCCUCUUGCAUGACCGAGGCCACUAUGUCCUGUGUGACUUUGGAAGCGCCACCAACAAAUUCCAGAAUCCACAAACUGAGGGAGUCAAUGCAGUAGAAGAUGAGAUUAAGAAAUACACAACGCUGUCCUAUCGAGCACCAGAAAUGGUCAACCUGUACAGUGGCAAAAUCAUCACUACGAAGGCAGACAUUUGGGCUCUUGGAUGUUUGUUGUAUAAAUUAUGCUACUUCACUUUGCCAUUUGGGGAAAGUCAGGUGGCAAUUUGUGAUGGAAACUUCACAAUUCCUGAUAAUUCUCGAUAUUCUCAAGACAUGCACUGCCUAAUUAGGUAUAUGUUGGAACCAGACCCUGACAAAAGGCCGGAUAUUUACCAGGUGUCCUACUUCUCAUUUAAGCUACUCAAGAAAGAGUGCCCAAUUCCAAAUGUACAGAACUCUCCCAUUCCUGCAAAGCUUCCUGAACCAGUGAAAGCCAGUGAGGCAGCUGCAAAAAAGACCCAGCCAAAGGCCAGACUGACAGAUCCCAUUCCCACCACAGAGACUUCAAUUGCACCCCGCCAGAGGCCUAAAGCUGGGCAGACUCAGCCGAACCCAGGAAUCCUUCCCAUCCAGCCAGCGCUGACACCCCGGAAGAGGGCCACUGUUCAGCCCCCACCUCAGGCUGCAGGAUCCAGCAAUCAGCCUGGCCUUUUAGCCAGUGUUCCCCAACCAAAACCCCAAGCCCCACCCAGCCAGCCUCUGCCGCAAACUCAGGCCAAGCAGCCACAGGCUCCUCCCACUCCACAGCAGACGCCUUCUACUCAGGCCCAGGGUCUGCCCGCUCAGGCCCAGGCCACACCCCAGCACCAGCAGCAACUCUUCCUCAAGCAGCAACAGCAGCAGCAACAGCCACCGCCAGCACAGCAGCAGCCGGCAGGCACGUUUUACCAGCAGCAGCAGGCCCAGACUCAGCAGUUUCAGGCAGUACAUCCAGCAACCCAGAAACCAGCAAUUGCUCAGUUCCCUGUGGUGUCCCAAGGAGGCUCUCAACAGCAGCUAAUGCAGAAUUUCUACCAGCAGCAGCAGCAGCAGCAACAACAACAGCAACAGCAACAGCUGGCCACAGCCCUGCAUCAACAACAGCUGAUGACUCAGCAGGCUGCCUUGCAGCAAAAGCCCACUAUGGCAGCAGGACAGCAGCCCCAGCCACAGCCAGCUGCAGCCCCACAGCCAGCCCCUGCCCAGGAGCCAGCGAUUCAAGCCCCAGUAAGACAACAGCCAAAGGUUCAGACAACCCCACCUCCUGCCGUCCAGGGGCAGAAAGUUGGAUCUCUCACUCCACCCUCAUCCCCCAAAACCCAACGUGCUGGGCACAGGCGUAUUCUCAGUGACGUAACCCACAGUGCAGUCUUUGGGGUCCCUGCCAGCAAAUCAACCCAGCUGCUCCAGGCAGCUGCAGCUGAGGCCAGUCUCAAUAAGUCCAAGUCUGCAACCACCACUCCAUCAGGCUCUCCUCGGACCUCUCAACAAAACGUUUAUAAUCCUUCAGAAGGGUCUACGUGGAAUCCCUUUGAUGACGAUAAUUUCUCCAAACUCACAGCUGAAGAACUGCUAAACAAGGACUUUGCCAAGCUUGGGGAAGGCAAACAUCCCGAGAAGCUUGGAGGCUCAGCUGAGAGUUUGAUCCCAGGCUUUCAAUCAACCCAAGGUGAUGCUUUUGCUACGACCUCAUUUUCUGCUGGAACUGCUGAAAAAAGGAAGGGUGGGCAGACUGUGGACUCUGGCCUCCCGCUUCUAAGCGUGUCUGAUCCUUUCAUUCCUCUUCAAGUACCUGAUGCACCAGAAAAACUAAUUGAGGGACUCAAAUCUCCUGACACUUCUCUUCUGCUCCCUGACCUCUUGCCUAUGACAGAUCCUUUUGGUAGCACUUCUGAUGCUGUAAUUGAAAAAGCUGAUGUUGCUGUUGAGAGUCUCAUACCAGGACUGGAGCCCCCAGUUCCCCAGCGCCUCCCAUCUCAGACGGAAUCUGUGACCUCGAAUCGCACAGAUUCUCUCACCGGGGAAGAUUCCCUGCUUGAUUGCUCUCUGCUCUCUAACCCUACUACUGACCUUCUGGAAGAGUUUGCCCCCACAGCAAUCUCUGCUCCAGUCCAUAAAGCUGCAGAAGAUAGUAAUCUCAUCUCAGGUUUUGAUGUCCCUGAGGGCUCGGACAAGGUGGCUGAAGAUGAGUUUGACCCUAUUCCUGUAUUGAUAACCAAAAACCCACAAGGUGGGCACUCUAGAAACAGCAGUGGGAGCUCUGAGUCCAGUCUUCCCAACCUAGCCAGGUCUUUACUGCUGGUGGAUCAGCUCAUAGACCUGUAGCCGUGACCCAGUAGCAGAUGCAGUUCUGUAACCUUCAUACCGUAAAAUACAUUUUCAUUACGGAGUUAUGAAAAAAAUGAUUUUUUUAAAAAAAUCUGCAAAUAAGGGGCCCUCCAGCCCUUUUCUCCUACCCCUUGCCUUCUCCUGUAGAAAUGAUAAGGAAAGAAAAUCACUUUGGCCCUCCAGAUAUUCCUUGGCCAGUUCCUCCUUGUUAGUUUGCUGUGUUUUCUCAUUACCCUUCUUCAAUAGCAUUAUCUUAAAUCAAGCACUAGAUGCCAUGAGCUUCACCUCUGCUGGAAUCAACUCCACCAAAAGCUUAACUGUAACUGAAACUAGUGAAUUGACACUUUUGUCUCGUUCUUGCUAGGAAUGGCCUCCCAGAUCAAUUCUCCCAACCCCCGUCUCCUUUGGCCAGAUGCUGAUGAAUGUAUUUCCCUGUUUUUGCUUUUUAUCCUGAUGCAUUAUCAUGAGGACAUGGCUACUUCAGUUGGUCUUAACUCUAGGCAGUAGCCUGGAGAUGGGUGUGUGGUUUAAGAAAGGGUAAAACUUACUGACUGGUAGUAUAUAUUUGAGAAGAGAAAUUGAGCCCAGCUCUAGCCAACCAACUUUGACCUUGUUUGAUCAUAGACUUAGCCAAGGGAUUUUACACCCCAUGCAACCUGCCCAGCAUUCGUCCAGCUUUCUGGCUUCCAUUGAACCGUGAUUUCUCAGAUCUGGAGACGUGACUGCAAGUAUUUGAGAUCCUUGGAUACAAUGUGUACGUUAUAUAAAUCCCAAGUAUUGCCAUUCCUUUUCAUGUUAACUGUUCCAAGUGGGAUCUCAGAAUUAGACCAAAACAAGACGGUGGUAAUAUGAUACCUUUUAUUAGAAGACUUUUCACUGGGGCGGGGGUGGGGGGAGGAUGGGGAGGGGAAGGAAUUGUAGCAGAAACAGAUGUAUUUUUCUUGUGAUUUUUAUUUUGAAUCAAAUAUUGUAAAUUGUGUAUAAAUGAAGAUGCUGAAUAGUUCUGUUUCCACUUGGCAUUUCAAGUCUGAUAUCAGGUGUCUGUACAGGGUUUUGAUUUCUUUCCCUUGUAUAACUACACAACAAUCCUACAGUGUAACAUAUGGAAUCAUUUUGAAUAGACUUGUGUGCUAUAAGCUUUCAGCAGGUCCUCUGUCUCUAGAAUAAGCAUGUUGUUUAUUUUCAGAUAAUCAGAAAUAAGUGUGCUGACAAGCUGGACACAAUCUGGGUGUGCCCAGCUUACCUUUCUUUCUGAUGUUUAAAUUGAAGGCUGCAGCCAAUGGAAUAUGUUCAGCUGGUUUUCCUUGGCUUCCUAGAUUAAAAAAAAAUAAUAAAGCAUAGUUCUUUAUUAACUUUAGGAUAUUGUUCAUAAAAUAAAUAAAGGCCCCUGCACUAACAUGACAACAUGCCUCAUGGUCACCCUCUCUAUAUGUACUUACUCAUUAAAGUGUAUUUUAUUUCCUUAUGUGGAAAGCACUUUUAUAAAAUCACCCUUUUGAAAAGAAGUGGGCACAGAGAACCCCACUCCUGUUCUUUUCCUCUAGUGCCAUUGUCCAUCAUCAAAAGGGAAACUCUUAGUUAAUCAGAUCUGUACAAAUAAAAUUCCAAGUCCAUUUGCUUGUUUUGCUAUCUAGUACUUUUGUUUCUUCUUCCUCACAUUUGCACUUUAUGGGGGAAAAAAGUUUAACAGCAACAACAGCCUAUAAAACACUGCAUUCUGGAGGGCAAGGUUUGACCCUAGGAAUGUGCGAGUAGCCUUUGAAAGGCAUUGGAGGAAAAGUCUGAAUCUUCCAGCCUUCCUUCUGUCUUUAAAUACUUCCCGUGCUGGCUGAAACAAGAUGAGCUAGGUAAAGGCCUCUAGUUGAAUAACAGACCAUUUCCAAAACUGAGAGAGGCACAAGCUUCCUGCCGAGGAUUAAAAAGCAAAAGAUAUCCACGAAGGGCUCUCUGUGGUUGGAUAGCAGUGAAAAUAGGACUUGGUUUACCCCUUUAUGGACAGGAAAAUUGCUGCAGGUCAGAAUUGUAUUCUCUUUCCUGGACAUAGAAAGAAUGUAUAAAUUAAUGAAGGAAAUGUUUAUUUUUAAAUAAGAAUAAUGUUUGAGUUCUAUGUUUUCAUAUUUGAUUUUUUUCGUAUAUACAUGUUAGAAAUAUAAUGAAAUAUCUAGUUUCUCAAUUUAAUUGAAACUAUGAAGAGUACAGUUUAGAAAUUAGGUAUCUCUAAAUUGUUCUUUUCAUAUAUUACCCAUAAUUACAUUGAAAUAUAUUAUCUAGUCAUUUGGCUCAGUAAAGCUUAAUGGAGGCAGUUAAUGAAAAUGAGCAGACUAGAAGCCAGAGACGGCAGUAGAAGCCUAAGGGAGAUAAUGACAAGAAAUUGUCUUGGGCUUAUUUAGAGUAAGGCCUCCUCAAAGGGGAGAACUAUUUUUCUGUUAAGGAACACAUAUGAGUGCUUUGGUAAACGGAGCCUUCCUUGGUUUAGAGCAUCAUCCCUGAGCUGAAAGAGUUUAUUUGAGUUGAGCAUAGUGUCCUGGUACCUGUGGAAUCAUAGCCUGAGCUACAAAGGGACCUUUGAGACCAUCCUCUAGUCCACCAUCCUCUUCAUUUUACAGGUGUGGGACCUGAGCUGGAUUGAACAGGGUCGGGGGAGAAGAGGCCUGGGCAGGACAGGCCACCUGGGAUCUCAUCCUGGCCCUUGCCAGCCACUGGCUGAGUGACCUUCAGCAGGCACUUCACCUCUCAGAGUUGCUGUUCCUUAGAGUUAUACGAUGGGUUUGGACUAGAUGGUCUUUAAGAUUAUAGAAGUAUAGGGUCCUAAGUAUAUAUUAUUAUAUUGAGAAGGGCUAUGAAGGAUUUAUAUAAUCCUGAUGUUCUUCAGUUAUCUUCUGUAGUUCCUGCUAUUACGGUAGCAGUGUUUACAUUUUAAAGAAUUAUAAUGGGCUUUUACUAACUUGCUCUUUCUUGAUUAUCUGAAUAGAAGCCUAAAUCAUAAUCUUAGAGAUUUUCCUUUUUAAGUAUUACAGAAACACAUGCGUGGACACACACCUACCUAUUCUAAUAAAAUGGUAUCAGAAGAUUUCUUUUUAAAUGUAUAAUCAGGCAUCUACCAGUUUAAAACGGGCAAAUACUAUAAGCAUAUGUUUCUGAUUUGCUUUUAUUCCAGCUAUGUAAGAGGAGUAACUAUAGCAGAAAACAUGACAAAUUGAUUUUUCCCUUUACAACAUUCAAAUGAGUCCCAAUGUUUUCAAAAAUACAUACCUCAGAGGAGAUAAGGCUUAAGUGGACACUUCUAAGUAUGAUUAUAAUUAUUAUAAUUAAUGAUUUCUUUAGCAGACAUAUCAGAAUUUUGACAUCUAAUUAAGUGUUGUUCCCCUCAAUGUCAUCUAGUUUUACUUAAGAAGUUAAUACUUAUUCUAAUGAUGCUGCCAUCCUUAAAGUUAUUUUUGAAACUCCUCUCCUUAGAAAUAAUAUCAAGGAAGGUAAUAAGGUAUAAGAAAAUCAGCUAUAUUAUUUAAUUAGUAUCACUUUGAGAAAGCACCUGGAAGUAUAUUCUUUCUUUGUCUACUUUUUCUACUACUCUUGGUUCUGAGUAACAUUUAGCCAUUUCCAGAAAGCAAAUUCAACCCUGUAAGAUGAAGAGUGGUUACUGUUGAAGACAGUAAAAAGGAUAAUCCACAAAAAAUUCUCAGAGAGGACCUUAUAAUAGAAAGUGAACAUGAUUAAGACUUAAUUUCUGUAAUUUUCUGAAUAAGGAAACUUCUGUGAUUCCUUAGUCUUUAGAAUGGUUUAAAACAUUGAAAGAUAUGGGUAUUAAAACACCUCUGAAAGAAGUUGUCACUUUGUUCAGUGUUAUUUGAUAUUGGACUUCGCUCUUCCUGAAUUAGAAUUACACAACUUGGAUUGCUAAUACUUGUGGAAAAACAAACCCAAGAAACGAACUACUUUCUCAAGAUGUAAUAUUUGUUUUAUUAUUAAUACUUUUGGUUGUUUUGAUUACUUAUUUCCUACUCUCCUGACAGAUAAUUGAUCAACCAAUAUAACCUUCCCCAGGUUAGGAACAGUUCUGCCUUCAGCAGUGCUGUGGGAAUGAAGGGAUCUUUGGGGCUGACAGCCUAUGAUGUGGAGGGAUCUGCACUCAGCUAAAUAAAUACAUGCUAUAGAUACCUUGGGCCAAAAUAAAGUCUCUCUUGAUAAGGUUUUUCUGUGAUUUCCCAGAGUCCUUAACCUUCUCUGUCUGCAAGAUUAUCAGGCUCCCAUAGCCACUAACUUUGAGCUUUGGGAUGAAAAUGACAGGAUUGCCCAGUGUGCCGGGUUAAGCAAAUUAGAGGCUGCCUGGCAGAACAGAAAAACUAUCACAUGAAUAUUUAGAAUGGAAGCUUUCCUGAAACACUCCAGAUACUGCAAAGCUAUCUUUAUUCCUCUCUAAAGGCUAUAAUUUUAUCAACACAAAGUCAGCCUUUUCUUUUUCCACAUUAGUAAUGUUUCUGAAGUUGGAUGUGCUUAGAUUUCUUAAAUCAGAAUGAGUGCUAGGAAAUCUAUAACAAGAAACCUCUUUUGCUUCUCCCAGAUUUCCUUUCACUAAUACGGGAUAGGGAGGCUCCUUGGGUAAUGCUAACCUAUGCAAAGAAGUUACCAAAUGGUGGUAGUUGCUAGAAUUAAAGACACGUUCUUGGUUCACACUUUGAUGUAGUGACCUGAAUUUACUCUUUUCCUGUGAGUAUUCUACUCUGCCCUAUUGCACUCUCCUUUGUCAUGUGGAUGUGUGUUUAUCAUAGGUCUUUAACGCGUCCUUCCCAAGAAGACAAAGCAUACAGUUGUACAUGAAGAUAUCUUAUGCAGUAAAAACGUGAAAUUUGAACAUUGCUGCACAAGUAUUGUAUAAAAAAAAGUCUGUAAAGAACUUUCUUAUGUAAACAUACAGGGGAAUAAAGACUUUUAUCUGUUCAAAUGGGAGCAUGAUGUUUAGAGAUGUAAAUAACUUAAAAUAAGUUGCUCUUUUCCUGAGCUGAAAACCCACUUUUUUGCAGAAAGGAUUUAAUCACAGUAUUGAGUGACAAUAAGUACCUGGGCACAAGAAAAGUAUAGCUACACACUGAGGACAUAUUAAUGAAUCAUGGCUACCUGAGAGAGUAAAACCCCUGUUUUAGUCUCAAGGAGAAUAAGACGCCUGCCAGCCUACACUGGAUAUGACCAGACUCAGGGUUGUAAAAUGGAGCGCAGGUUUGCAGCUUCCCUCCUCUAACUUAAUCCCUAAUAUACCCAGGCCAACUUAAUUAAACAUUUUGUGUUGGCAAGAAUAAUUUUAUCCCCAGUGAGAAAACUCACUCAUUUAAUUGCCUCAUUGGCCUGAGAGGCACAGCUGGCCAUUUUUGGCUUCCAUGAGGUCCCUCAUUUCCCAGUCGUGGGUUUUAAUGCAGCUACCUAAUAUAUGGUGGAACCAAAUGCUUAAUUUUGUUAUGUGAGCUAGAAGGUCAUGGUAAUUAUUAGUUUGAUGUACGUCUCUUGAUUUCCCCAGUUUGGUUCUAAAAUUUUACGUUUCAAUUGCUGCUGCAUUUCCAAGUUCUUGUGAAGGGAUAUUUUGCUUUCUGUUUACUAACUAUAUGUGAGAAGGCUUCUUCUCAAUGCUCCAAGUCUUCGUUUUCUGUUUUUGGCAAGAAUCAUAUCUUUGAUACUCCCUGUAACCGUUCUUUCAGUUUUUGGUAUGAGGAAAAGUAAACUUCUGGUGUUGUGUGAUGUAUUUCAUUAAGGAAUAUCCAGCCUGACAUUUAAGUCUUCAGAUUUUAAUUCUGUAGGGAGCAUUCUGAUGGCCCUCACUAUGUCAAUCAGAUGGAGUUUCCAGGGGAAACCCAUCCUAAAUGAUUCAGCACUUUGGGUUGCUUUGGAAGUGAAUAGGGAGCUGGUGAGGAUAGUUGCCAAGUUGUCAGGUAUUUUAGGAACUCCUUCUCUUCCCUGAAGCAUGUGAGUUCUUGCUGAAAUCUACAUAAUUUGGAGCCUCAAAAUAGACUAAUAUGGAGUUACCCAUAUUGAAAGUGUCAACGUGCCUAACCUGGCACACAGUCCUACAUCAGAGCAAGAAAAAGAAGUAUGUUUUGACUUCUUGCUUAAUUUUAUGUGUGAAACCAAAAUAAAAAGAGGCAUGAUCCAGUUUGAGGGAAUUAUAACAAAACCCUACGUUAGGCUCUAUGAUAAGUAAGACCCUGUGCAGACUAUGAAGCCAGGCCCUGGGCUUUAGCCCCUGAGGUACAACAGGCAGUGUUUACUGAGCUCUAUGGCCACAGGGUAUCUGCUAUGACGUGCCAUUGGUUACCAAAGGAACUGGGUCAAGGCAUGUGGUUAGGUUAGUAUAAAUCCUUCAAUGCUAGUAAAGAGACUGCUUCAAACACGUUUUCUUGUUGACACAAUGCUACCUUCAUAUAAAGGAACUGUUCACCCUGAAAACACAUUUUCCCUGUAAGAACACAUUCACAUACUCAAAAAAAGACUUUUAUCUGCCAACAAGAUUUAAUGGUUACCUUCUGUUUCUAGUAUAUUUGGAAUUUAUCCUUCUCUCGACUACCUUGUUUCUGGUGCUGCCACCACCAGAAUUCCUUAAGGGAAUGUGGAGGUCUGGGCUUCCCCCAUAUUCUCUGGCAUUUCUUUGCCCUUCAGAGUGCCAGGCCUGGAGAGUUGCAAAGUGUGGUUGCUCUCCGCCUCAGCCACACUGUACCUCCUCUAACAAGAAUAGAAAGGUUAAGGGACUUGGCCUUCUCAGGACAACCCUUUAAAUGUACUUUUCCAUUCCUACAAAGCCUGUUGAUGCUGAAAGAAAGAUAGGAAAUAGCUCUUGUCCUUGUUUUGAAGGACAGGAGACUAAUUUUCCCUUCAAACUUGAUAUUCUGGUGUUUUUGUGACUGUUUUUGUAAAUUAUUCAAAGUUGUUGGAAUUUUAAGUCUGAUUUUCCCAGUACUCAUCAUGAAGGUCAUAGAAUAUGCUCUGAGUUGGAAGGUUUUCCAAAUGGGUUCUCGACCAAAAACCCACUUUUUAACAAAUAAUUUUGAUGGGUUAGACAUGUUCUUCCAUCCUCUCCAACCCUGAAUAUGGGCACAUACACACACCCCUUGGUACUUCCUAGUUCUCAAAAUGUAAUCUAGCACUUCAGGCAUCCAAAGUGCCCCUGGUUCAAUAGAUAGCUGCUUUUUUGCCAGUCUCUGUGCACAAAUUGUUUUAACUGAAUUCAGUUUAAAUUUCCAAAAAACACUGACUCUGUUCAAACUAGUGUUCAUUGGAUUAUUGACCUGUAUGAUGCCAGAGUUGGUCACUGGCUUGACUAAGUUUUCCAUUUUUUUUCCCUAAGAGAUAUUUUGCUCUCCUGCAGAACAAGCUUAAUAACAUCAACUUUCAAGGUAGUUUUGGAAGAUGAGAAAUUGUGCUUUUGUUUUGGCAACUGAAAACUUUGUCCAACUGAUACUAUGUGAGGAAGGUGGUUCAAGGAGUUUUAGGGCCCUCUUGUCCUUCUUUAAGGCUCUGCAAACCUUAUUUUGGAAAACUUAUUUUUCUCCCUUUUAUUUGAAUUUCCUCCCAGAAAUUAUCAUCUUGGUAUCACUGAGACAAAUCUAAUAUCAAUUUACUUGCCUGAGAAAUUAGGAUUAUGUCUGUCCACAUAAAUCGCAAGGAAGAAGGUAUUCUGUUUAUUUCCUGUCCACUGACUGAUGCUUUCGUAUCACCAUGUAGCUGCACAUACUAAAAUUAUAAUACAAGGAAAAAUUUAUUCUUUUCAAAAUCUUAUUCUUCAAAUACUAUUCUGAAAGCCAUUUGGCACCAGUACAGAAUUUAACUUAACGCCCCAAUCUGGAAUUCACUGAACGCAUUCAAACUGUUAGAAAGGAAAAUAAAAAUGGAGGACAAACACAUUUUUGUUCUGUUUCUGAAAACAAUAUUUAAGGUCAGAACUGUUUAAAAAGAAGCACUGCUAAAAAGUUAUAGGAUUCAGAGAAACAUAGUAUUUUUGUACAGUAUCUUAUAAAAUGUUCAGACCUCUCUCUACAUUCUCUUUACAAUGUAAUGUCUCUAAGUGACUGGUUUCCCAAUAAACUGAUUUUAAUGCCUCUUCUGCUGUGGUCUGUGUGCUUAAUUCAUGCAGAAACUUUAGCAGGGGAUAAUUUUUGGCAGAAAUUUCUGCUAGCUAAUGGUUUGCAUAGGAGGGGAGAGGGUCAGUAUGGGAAGGGGAUCAUUGAGUUCCAUCUCUACAGAGGUUCUGGGUCAUCUAUGGCUCCAAAUCAUUGUAUCUAAUAUUCUUAUCCUGGUGGGUUGGGAAACUCCAGUAGUAUCUCUUUACUGAGCCCAUGAUGAAAUGAUACCUUUACCCCCAACCACCCUUUCUCUGGAUUCUUCUUGCUUAGUUACAUAUGCCUUUUUCCUGCCCUCUUGCUAACAUGUGCCCAAUGACAUACUUCUAACCUGCUAAUAUUUCUUGGAAGGUAAGCUCUCUUGCAUUCUGAUAAUUGUCUAUUUGAUUUUAAAAGCCAGAGCACCCUGAGGCACCUCUACCUAGAUAGAAAUAGACUAGUAUAUUGGAGUUUGCUAAUGCUUCUGUAAUGGCCCAUGCAUUUUACUCCUUCUGCUUAAAGAACUUUAUGGCAGAUUCAUUUAAGCAGAGGAGAUCUUUAUGAACUUAGAAGACUGAAAACAAAAUUCUGGGGCAACUCCAGCUGAAGGUGAUUUAUUUGGUCUGAUUUUGAUGCUGUAUGCUCCCCUCAGAAGGUACCUUCAGUAUUUAUAUUUUGGGCACUCGUAUGCUCUUUGAGUAGUGCUUGUGAUGUAAGUCAUCAAGUAAACUUGCAUUUAUCAAGCAGCCACAUUCUGCUUCUUUUCAGAGAGUUUGUCCCUCUGCAUGUGGCGCGGAUGACCACAUGCCAGAUUCUGAAUUGAGUCAUCCCCAGACAGUGUUUCUACAUAAUCCAAAACUGUCAUGGUAUAUGUGGAGAUGAAUGACUGGGUUUGUUUUCAUUCCAUAAUGAGCCAGUGCCAGGUAGAGCAGGUGUCCGUGCCUGGCCCUGUGUGUAGGAGCAUUGCAUAGUUACGCUGAAUGUCUGUGUGCCUAACAUCUUCAUCUCCUUUCCUGUACGUCGUGCCUAUCAUGUUCCAAAACGUGAGACAGUGGUUGAUUGUGUUCCAGUUUGUGUGCAGUUUCCUUGCCUGACUUUUAUUUUUAUGUUUUUCCUGUUGCAUUUUCAACAUCUAUUAUUUGGUCCCACAAUGUUUUUGCCGCGGGUUGACCAUUAAAUGUUCCAAAUAGAGUUGAAUUGACCUACACAUUAAUUCUGCAUUUUAUGCUUUUCUAGAUCUCCAGAGGGAGUCCAAUCCCUGUCCUGUAAUAACUGUAGAGCACUUUAAAGAAUCACUGGGUGUUAAAGGCCUUCCGCUGUAUCCAGACCCCUCCAGAGUACCUGGCACAAAGACUCAGAACAACUUAGAAUCUGACUACUUGGCCAGAGAUGGCCCUUCAAGCAACAGCUCAUUCCACAGCAGCGAAGAGGAAGGGACUGACCUUGAAGGAGACAUGCUGGACUGCAGUGGGUCUCGGCCUCUCCUUAUGGAGUCUGAAGAAGAAGAUGAGAGCUGCAGACCCCCCCCGGGGAAGCUGGGAGGAGCCGUUCCAUUCGCUCCACCAGAAGUCUCUCCUGAGCAAGCAAAGACAGUGCAAGGUGGAAGAAAGAACCAGUUUCAAGCCUUCACACAGCCAGCCACUGAUGGGCUCAGUGAGCCAGAUGUUUUUGCCAUAGCUCCCUUCAGGAGCUCAAGGGUUCCAAAUGAUGACAUGGACAUUUUCUCCAAAGCCCCAUUUGUCUCCAAGAGCAGUAUGGCUCCUUCCCAGCCAGAGGAGUCAGACGUGUUUUUGAGAGCUCCUUUCACUAAGAAGAAAAGCAUGGAGGAGUUAACAGUUAUCCAAUGCACCUCCCAGGAGCUGCCUGCACAGACCGGUCUCCUCAGUCAGACAGGUGAUGUCCCCCUGCCCGCGGGCCGUGAGAGAGCUGUGUACACCUCUGUCCAAGCUCAGUAUUCCACAGCUGGUUUUGUGCAACAGUCUAACCUCCUGUCCCAUUCUGUACAAGCAGCAGACCAUCUGGACAGCAUCUCUCCCAGGGGAUCCUGCCUGGAAUCUGGGGGUCAUUCUAAUGACAGAAACAAAGGACCUCAGCUCCAGAAAGAAGCUGUCUCAGGCCCCAUGGCUGGCAAACCAUUCCGCCCCCAGUCCUUAUCCAAGUAUUCCCGUCACUAUAGCCCAGAAGACGAGCCAAGUCCAGAAGCCCAGCCCAUUGCUGCCUACAAAAUUGUUUCACAAACCAACAAGCAGUCGAUAGCUGGGUCUGUUUCUAUCACAUCCCUUUCCUCCAGGACUACGGAGCUGCCAGCUGCUGAUCCAUUUGCUCUAGCACCCUUCCCUUCAAAAUCAGGCAAGAAACCCUAGGAGCAAAACCUGAGCCUCAAGCCUCUUGUCUCUAUCCCACCCUCAAUACCCGCCAUGGCACUCCCAGCUUAGCCUUCUGAAGAAGAAAUAUUAUCAGUUCUUAUAUUUCAAUUCCCUGCGUCAGAGCAGAAUUUCUUGAGUCAACAAACUCAGUUGCAGUGAUAUUUAGUUGAAGCCCCUUUAAGUUAUGUUCAUUUUUGUUUGUUUGUUUGUUUGUUUAUAUUGAUUUCUGGACUUGGAGGCAUUUUCAUCUCCUUCACAGAGGUCAUCCACUUCCACCAAGAACUCUGCUUUCCCCCCGCCCCACCCACAGAAACUGUUUAAAUCCUGAAAUACUUCUUCACCCCAAUCCCAAAGGGGCCCUAUUGUUGCUAGUUUUAAUUCCUGUAGCUCCUGUUCUAAGUCAUGCCCAUCGAAGAAUCAAGAUUAGUCCCUCCACUAAAUCAAGAUUUAGUACUCUUGAAAAGGGGAGAUGUCUGGAAAGAAGAGCAAGAUAAAAACCCUGCACAUCAACAGGAAGUAUAAUCCUGCAGUUACUAAUAAUUCCUGUAGAAGCAGCAGCUCUAGGAGUCUCCAGAUCUGAUUCUCAGUCUGUGUGCAAGCCAGGCUGGCUCUCGUGCAUGACUGUCUAUGGGUGUGGAAUGUACGUCAGAGCCUGUGUAGAGAUACAGGCAGAUGGGCUAACUCCUCAUGUCUAGUCAUGCUGGCAGGGCUUUCCCCACAUCCAUGCUUUUGAAAUUAGUGUGAGUGUACAGGUUUGUGUGUGCAUGUAUACGUGUGUGUGCACAGGAAGCAUUUCCACUUGAGGGAAAUCCUGCCCCAUCAUGCCUACCUCCACAAUGAAAUCACUCGUUUUUUGGUGUUUGCUCGCCUAACUGACUUGAACCCCAUUUUAUUUAUUUAGUUUUUUUCUCAUGGCAAAGUAGAAUACGUUGGAAGGUGUAGGGAAAUCCUGCUGGAACUGGUGUUUCAGAGUAAAUCUUUUUUCUCUCCGGAAUUUCUUGUUUUGCUAUUAACAAAUUAUAUUUACCUGAUUAUGAAAAAUUAAUUUUCCUUAUACAUUUUCCCCUUACAACACUAGAAAAGAGCACCUUGUUACAGUUCCGGCCUCUCAGUAUGUGGGCUAAAUGCCAGCAUUAGGGAAUUCAUUAAUCAUGAGACUAGGCUACAAACUAGGCUUGCUUGUUUUGGGGUGGUUUUGUUGUUGUUGUUGUUGUUGUUGUUGUUGUUUCCAAAUCUCUACUGCCUUUUGAGGAAAUGUAAAUCUGAGACAUGGAAAUAAGUGUUUGGGAGAAUGGAAAAGAGCUGAAUCAGGUAGGCAUGAAAACUUUUACAUUCUCUAUCCUCUUUAGAUGUUGAAAUAGGCCAGACAGGUUAACUGAUGUUUUUUAAAAUUGUCUUUUAUUUCUGGAAAGAUCUGACUUAUUCCUAGCUUUUUUCAUACCCUUUAUUAUUAGUGCCUUAAAAUAAAGCUGGCCAGGUGCAGUGCCACACACCUGUAAUACCAGCAUUUUGGAAGGCUGAGGCAGGAGGAUCAGUUGAGCCCAGGAAGUUCAAGACCAACUCUGGCAACACAGCGAGACCCUGUCCCUUCAAAAAAUAAAUAAAAAAAUAGGCUGGGCAUGGUGGCUCACACCUGUAAUCCCAGCACUUUGGGAGGCCAAGGUGGGCAGAUCACAAGGUCAGGAGUUUGAGACCAGCCUGGCCAACAUGGUGAAACCCCAUCUCUACUAAAAAUACAAAAAAUUAGCUGGACGUGGUGGUGCACACCUGUAGUCCCAGCUACUCAGGAGGCUGAGGCAGGAGAAUCGCUUGAACCCGGGAGGCAGAGGUUGCAGUGAGCAGAGAUUGCGCCACUGCACUCUGGCCUGGGCGACAGAGCGAGUCUAAAAAAUAAAAUUAAAUAAAAUAAUGAAAAAAAUUAGCUGGGUAUGGUGACAUAUGCCUGUAGCUACUCAGGAGGCUGAGCUGGAAGGAUCACUUGAGCCCAGGAGUUUGAGGCUGCAGUGAGUUGUGAGUCCAGCCUGGGUGACAGAGUGAGACACUGUCUCCAAAAAUAUAAUAAUAAAAAUAAAGCCUGUAUCUCAAUGGGAAGAUUUCUGCUAAGGCAGUUCAACUCACUGGAAAGAACUGCUGCAUUAGGUUUCAACUUUAAUGCUUUCUGUUACUUCUAGUAAAGGUUAAGUGAUUUUUCCAUUAGCUGUAGAAGUUUGGAGAGCUAUUUACCAAGCCAGAUCAAUGAUUUAAAAAUUAUUGGAAAUUCAUCUAAGAAUCAAGUCUGAAUGCCCAAUUCUAUUGCGGUUGAUUAGGUGUGAUAUUCUUUAAAGUUCAGGAAUAUUGGCAGUAAAAAAUGAGCAGCUACUUUUCAAUACUUUGUCCUUUUUUGGUGGUCUCUGCCUAUUUCAAAUGUCCUGAUCAAAAGAUAAAUAAUUGGCACUGUGCCAAGGUUUGGUUUUCCAACUAAGGUUUCAACUGUGCCAGAAACCUAUGUCCUUCACUUUGGUGGAUGCUAAAUGUUAUUCUAAGAAUAUGCUUUUUCCCAAUUCUCCUUUCUGAUUUUUAUGUAUUAGUGGAUGCAAAAUUGUCUUUCUAGUUGAAUGAAUAAUUUCGGCUAAUGCACGUGGAACUUUGCACCCCAGAUUCUUCCCAUGGUCAUUAUCAAGUGAAGCCCUCAAAAACAUGAGCGAAGAGCCUAGAAAUACUCAGGGAGAUUUCUCACCCCAACUCAGAAAUUUUUUUUUUUUUUUUCAAGACGGCGUCUUGCUCUGUCGCUCAGGCGGGAGUGCAGUGGUGUGAUCUCGGCUCACUGCAACCUCCAUUUUCCGAGUUCAAGCGAUUCUGCCUCAGCCUCCCGAGUAGCUGGGAUUAUAGGCACACACCACCGCGCCUGGCUAAUUUUUGUAUUCUUAGUAGAGAUGGGGUUUCACCAUGUUGGCCAGGUUGGUCUUGAACUCUUGACCUUGUGAUCCACCCACCUUGGCUUCCCAAAGUGCUAGGAUUACAGGCGUGAGCCACCGCACCUGGCCCAGAAAUUCUUUUUUUUUUUUUAAAUUAUUAUUAUACUUUAAGUUUUAGGGUACAUGUGCACAAUGUGCAGGUUAGUUACAUAUGUAUACAUGUGCCAUGCUCGUGUGCUGCACCCACUAACUCGUCAUUUAGCAUUAGGUAUAUCUCCUAAUGCUAUCCCGCCCCCCUCCCCCCACCCCACAACAGUCCCCAGAGUGUGAUGUUCCCCUUACUGUGUCCAUGUGUUCUCUUUGUUCAAUUCCCACCUAUGAGUGAGAACAUGCGGUGUUUGGUUCAGAAAUUCUUAAAGUAAGAGAUCAUUCUAAUUCCCCUUUCCAAAUAUUCAGGAUUAUCUCUGUAACAGCCCAGCAAAAUGUUUUUCCUUUGGUUAUUUGAUAAUUCCCUUCUAAUCAAGUGACUAUUUUAAUUCUCAAGGUGCAAAUCAGGAUAAAAUCAUGGUGAUUUUACUACAUAGUUGAAUACUUCGUCAAGUAUGAGCUUGUAUCCUUUUUAAAUUUUUCACUGGAGGCCAGGCGCGGUGGCUCACGCUUGUAAUCCCAGCACUUUGGGAGGCCGAGGUGGGUGGAUCACUUGAGGGUAGGAGUUUGAGACCAGCCUGGCCAACAUGGUGAAACCCUGUCUCUACCAAAAAUACAAAAAGUAGCUGGGCGUGAUGGCACGCACCUGUAGUCCCAGUUACUAGGGAGGCUGAGGCAGAAUUGCUUGACCCAGGGAGGCAGACUUUGCAGUGAGCCAAGAUUGUGUCAUUGCACUCCAGCCUGGGCGAGAAGAGCAAAACUCCGCCUCAAAAAAAAAAAAAAAAUUGUCACUGGAGACAUGAUGGGUGGAGACUCUACAUACCUUCUUUGAAUACAGAAACGGAUGCAAACACAUGCAAAUUACUUUUUUUUUUUUUUUUGGUGAUGCAUGAAAAAACUUUGACUUGUGGAUUACAUUAAUUAUUAGUAACAGUUAGAUUCUGCCGACUUGUAUUACAGUAGGGUCUUAUUUCCUUAAAGAGAAAAAAAAAUACAGUCAUGCCCCACUUAAUGAUGAGGGAGACAUUCAGAGAAAUGCAUCCUUAGGUGAUUUUGUCAUUGUGUGAACAUCACAGAGUGUACUUAACACAAACCUAGAUGGCACGGCCUACUACCUACCUAGGCUAUAUGGUCCAGCCUGUUGCUCCUGGGCUACAAACCUGUACAGCAUGUUACUGUACUGAAUACUGUAGGCAGUUGUAACACAAUGGUAAGUAUUUCUGUAUCCAAACAUUUUAGACAUAGAAAAGGUACAGUAAAAAUAUGGUAUAAUCUUAUGGGACCAUCAUGGUAUAUGUGGUCCAUCAUUGAUGGAAUCGUUUUUAUGCAGCACAUGACUGUAUAUAAUCAACAAACAACUCUACUUUCUUGUUUUCGUUUGUUGUGUUUUUGCUUUACACAUUUGAUAGGGAACAUAGAAGUUGUGACCUUUCAUUUCAGUGGAAAGCAUUGAGCCAGAAUAUAUUUAUUCCUAAACCAUCGAGCCACACAUGCAUUGAUGAACCCUGAAAGAAUCCACAGUAAUUGACUAACAGGCAGUACUGAAUGAAAGAUGUCAUAUGUGGUGAAAAAUAUUUAAUAUAUCAGUUUCUUGGGCUCACAUACAGCCCUUUAGUUCCAAGUGCUUGGUUAGAUUAGAAAAUGGGAUGAACACAAUUUGAUGCUGAAGCAGCUGCUGAGCAGCACCCAGGGAGUCUAGGUCAUACGCCCUAUAUUGUUUUCGGCCCACUUAUUGUUGAGUUGAAAAGUCUCAUAUUUGUAGACUAGAGUGUAUGUGUUUAGAGGCUCAUGUUGUAUCUGAGUUUUCUCUGGCAACUAAGAUCUCUUUCUAAACGUUCUAGAAAGAUACUGGUAUCUUACUGGCCCAUUAUUUAGUAAGUUUUAGAAUACAUGUACAUCAGUGUUUUCAACUGCUUGGUGGACAUUUCACUGAUGCAUAAUCAAAGUAGCAGAUUAUAAUCAUCAGAGUGAUCUGACAAGGAAAUUCUGUAUUUGCUUCCAUAAAGAAAAAUAAUCAAAACAUAUAUCAGAUAUAAUAUAUAUGCAGUAUAUCACAUAGGAAAUUUUAUUGUAGGAAAUUAGAGAAGGAUGCUACUCAAUUCAUUCUCUAGCAGGAAGAAUACAGCUUAAAAAUCACUUGGGUCCCUUUAAUAAAGAAAAGUGUGAUUCUGUGUUGUGUGUUUGGAACUGAAAUUGGAGAACACGUGCCAGUCGACUGUGAAAUGGUUGCUGGAUAAAACCACAGAUGUGGUUUUAUCCGAGAAAUGUGGGACUGAAAUUAUUUUGAUGAGAGGUACAUAAGAGAGCUGCAGAAAAGACUGUAGCUUCUGAGGAGGCAGGAGUACCUUGUUAAUAUCCAAACCACCCCUGAGUUCUAAUGUUCCAACUCCACCUAAACGAGGAAUUGGAAACUUUAAAUGGAAUUAUCUAAUUUAAAUUCUUAGUUUUUUCUUUGUCUUUCUCAGCUGAUACUUGUAGUUUUGUUUUGUUUUUUAACCACCAAGAACACUUGCAAGUUUGUUACUGAAAACAUCACUAAAGGAAAAGAAGAGUUUCAAAAUGCUUGAAAAGUAGUAUGUGGUUGGGAAUUGUUUUUGUUCAAGUCCCUGGAAGUCCUCUUGGCUUAGCUCCCUUGUUCCUGUUCCCACUUCAUUUCCUUACUUAACAUUCCCCUAUUUUGAGCAUGUCAAUAAGUGCAUGAUGAAUGGCACAGUUGAAUGAUCAUGUUAACUUUAAUUGCUUCCUUUGUUGCUGUAAACAGUUUCUUGUUAAGUUUCAGCCAAGUCUGUGACAAUCUCACCAAAUAAGAAUGAAAUGGGCGGGGUGUGGUGGCUCACACUUGGAAUCCCAGCACUCUGGGAGGCUGUGUUGGGCCGAUCGCUUGAGCUCAUGAGUUCAAGACCAACCUGGGCAACAUGGCAAAACCUUGUCUCUACAAAAAAUACAAAAAUUAGCCAGGCAUGGUGGUGCACACCUGUAGUCCCAGCUACUUGGGAGGCUUAGGUGGGAGGAUGGCUUGAGCACGGGAGGCAGAGGUUGCACUAAGCCAAGAUCGUGUCACUGCACUCCAGCCCAGGCAAUAGAGCCAGACCCUGUCUCAAAAAAACAAAACAAACAAAACAUGAAUGAAUGAAAUGGCUCACCUUCCCUAUUAUGAACUAGAAGAAAGGAUGAAGGAAGGUUGGCAGGACCCCAGCCUUACUCUGUAGUGACAACCCAGAGGUACUUUUCCCGGAAUGCAGGGUCAAGUUUAUGUGUGAAGGGACUCUAGAAUAGCUGGUAAAAAUGGCUACAUGGUAACCAUUCUUGACUUAGUCCAGUAUUCCCAUAAUUUGUAAUUCCAUAAAUUUAUUCUCAGCUGUCCCCCAGCCAUUUCUAAUAGAAGGAUGUGUACCCCAGUUUUGACAAUGUUCUUGAAAUCAAGUUAGUGUUACCUGCAUUGCAUUAUAAUGGAACUAUAUGUACAUGUUAAAGGGAUCCGUUUGAUUCCUUUCGGCAAGGAAUUGCAAAAAUAGUUUUUACCAAUACCAGUUAAAAUAGGAUAGGUUAGACUUUGGGGGCAGGGUGAGACAGUGCAGCCUUUUCACUCUGAAAUGGCAAAUCAGCUGUACUCUUUGAGUCUACCAGAGAUUCCUAUUUGAGUGUGAAUGGGGUGUGUGUGUGUGUGUGUGUGCUCAUUCAUCUUCAUGCUUUCUUCCAUGGUGUUAAUUCAAGCUCUCCUAAUAAAGGUAUCCAAAGAGUACUGAGAAGUGACCAUAGGUAUUUGGCAUGAGUAAAUGUAGUUCCUUUUGCCAAAAAAACUCUCAAAAGUUACAACUGGAGUUCUUCGCGAUAAAAGGUUGGGGAAAUCAGCCAUGGCUUUAGCCUUGUUCCCAAGUACACAUCUUCUUAUCCACAAGGAUGAAACUCUGUAGGGCUCACCCUGAGGGCUCAUGUGUGGCAUUGAGAGGGUAGCAGUGACCAGAACACCACAAGGCCCACAAGAUGUUUUGAAUGAGGGAACAUUUAAUGUCAUUUGUUAGGAGAUAGAAACCAAAUAAUAAAGGACAAGGACCACGCUCAUUCCGUGGAGAAGAGGUGAACUCCCUCUGCUGACUAUUUGGAAUGGACUGAAUGAGGAGGUCUCUCCAGCCAGAAGGAGUAUUGAGGUCAUCAGGCCUCAGAAAACAAUGUACACAUAAUCUCGGGCUGUGAACAAGAGAAAGGAGGGGGGGAAACAUGAAAGUCAAUCUUAACAAUUUUUGCAAUACCUCUUAUUUGCAGACCAUUGGAUUUAUGUUAUUGCACUCUCGGUGUGAUUUAUCGUAUGUAUCUGAUAGGUUUUAUGAAUUGUUUUGAGUUGUAAACUCCUAUACCCUUUAUUAAAAUGGACCUAAUUAAGUGA